GUGAGCCUGGUGGUUGGCAGCUGGAGCCACGUCGGAGGGGGAAGUGUCGCAGCAUUCUCUGCAGGCAUCACAGACCUGAGGCAGUGGCCUCCGGAGGGCACUGGACAGAAACAGCCAUCCAAGUGGCUGAGUGGAGGGACCCUGCUCAAGUGCAGCUGCAGUGGCCGGGGUUUCCCUCAGGUAGGGAUCGGGGCGCCUUGUCGCCGCCAGCCACGUGUGGCGUCCGGUACAGUCAGCAGAGUGCAGGGUGCGGGCACCAGGAAAGGGGGCGCAGGGGAACUCCCGCGGGCCUCGCGUUUGCAAACUUCUCGCCUGGGCAGGAGGCGGUCGUGGGAAAGAAGGUGGAAGAGCGAGCUUUUUGGAACUGUGCACGGGACAGAUUGGACGCACACCCCUCGGGAGGCGCGAAGGCAUGGAAAAUUUGAAGCAUAUUAUCACCCUUGGCCAGGUCAUCCACAAACGGUGUGAAGAGAUGAAAUACUGCAAGAAACAGUGCCGGCGCCUGGGCCACCGCGUCCUCGGCCUGAUCAAGCCUCUGGAGAUGCUCCAGGACCAAGGAAAGAGGAGCGUGCCCUCUGAGAAGUUAACCACAGCCAUGAACCGCUUCAAGGCUGCCCUGGAGGAGGCUAAUGGGGAGAUAGAAAAGUUCAGCAAUAGAUCCAAUAUCUGCAGGUUUCUAACAGCAAGCCAGGACAAAAUACUCUUCAAGGACGUGAACAGGAAGCUGAGUGAUGUCUGGAAGGAGCUCUCGCUGUUACUUCAGGUUGAGCAACGCAUGCCUGUUUCACCCAUAAGCCAAGGAGCGUCCUGGGCACAGGAAGAUCAGCAGGAUGCAGACGAAGACAGGCGAGCUUUCCAGAUGCUAAGAAGAGAUAAUGAAAAAAUAGAAGCUUCACUGAGACGAUUAGAAAUCAACAUGAAAGAAAUCAAGGAAACUUUGAGGCAGUAUUUACCACCAAAAUGCAUGCAGGAGAUCCCGCAAGAGCAAAUCAAGGAGAUCAAGAAGGAGCAGCUUUCAGGAUCCCCGUGGAUUCUGCUAAGGGAAAAUGAAGUCAGCACACUUUAUAAAGGAGAAUACCACAGAGCUCCAGUGGCCAUAAAAGUAUUCAAAAAACUCCAGGCUGGCAGCAUUGCAAUAGUGAGGCAGACUUUCAAUAAGGAGAUCAAAACCAUGAAGAAAUUCGAAUCUCCCAACAUCCUGCGUAUAUUUGGGAUUUGCAUUGAUGAAACAGUGACUCCGCCUCAAUUCUCCAUUGUCAUGGAGUACUGUGAACUCGGGACCCUGAGGGAGCUGUUGGAUAGGGAAAAAGACCUCACACUUGGCAAGCGCAUGGUCCUAGUCCUGGGGGCAGCCCGAGGCCUAUACCGGCUACACCAUUCAGAAGCACCUGAACUCCACGGAAAAAUCAGAAGCUCAAACUUCCUGGUAACUCAAGGCUACCAAGUGAAGCUUGCAGGAUUUGAGUUGAGGAAAACACAGACUUCCAUGAGUUUGGGAACUACGAGAGAAAAGACAGACAGAGUCAAAUCUACAGCAUAUCUCUCACCUCAGGAACUGGAAGAUGUAUUUUAUCAAUAUGAUGUAAAGUCUGAAAUAUACAGCUUUGGAAUCGUCCUCUGGGAAAUCGCCACUGGAGAUAUCCCGUUUCAAGGCUGUAAUUCUGAGAAGAUCCGCAAGCUGGUGGCUGUGAAGCGGCAGCAGGAGCCACUGGGUGAAGACUGCCCUUCAGAGCUGCGGGAGAUCAUUGAUGAGUGCCGGGCCCAUGAUCCCUCUGUGCGGCCCUCUGUGGAUGAAAUCUUAAAGAAACUCUCCACCUUUUCUAAGUAGUGUAUCAAAAUCUAAACCAAGGAGUCUCUGGACAAGAAGCUGGGAGAGGCACAAACUGGACAUCUCUCUCUCUCAUAUCCUUCGGCAUUGGGUUAUCUAUGGGUGCAAGGAGUGGGCACGCUUCUCUGUUACAAAUAGAAAACGAUUCCAGUCAUACAGGACACAUCCCACUCCAAAUGAUAUUUCCAAAAACAUACCUCUGACAGUAACUUUGAUAGAUGGUUUGUCAAAUGUAUCUUUCUGGGUAUCCACACCUCUUGGCAAUGAAAUUUGCAGCUCCUCCCUUCCAUAAAUGAAGUCUCUUUCCCCACCAUUUGAAUCUGGGCUGGCACUGUGACUUGAUUUGAUCAAUAGAAUGUGGAAGAAGUGACUGUAUGCCAGUUCCAAGCCUAGGUUUCAAGAGGCCUUAUAAAUGUCUGUUGGAACCUUACCCAGCCAUGAACAUGUUGAGUGAGCAUGCUGGAGAAUGAGAGACCACAUGAAGCAGAAACAUGCUUUCCUAGCUGAAGUCAUACUAGCCCAACCAACAUGGCAGCUAACACAUGAAUGAGGCCAAUCAAGACCAGAAGAACCACUCAAGCAGAUCCCAGCCCAAAUUGCCCAUUCACACAAUCAGGAGCUAAAUAAAUUACUGUUGUCUUAACACUAA